GUGAUCUGUGAAAAUGGUUCGCUAUUCACUUGACCCGGAGAACCCCACGAAAUCAUGCAAAUCAAGAGGUUCCAAUCUUCGUGUUCACUUUAAGAACACUCGUGAAACUGCUCAGGCCAUCAAGGGUAUGCAUAUACGAAAAGCCACGAAGUAUCUGAAAGAUGUCACUUUACAGAAACAGUGUGUACCAUUCCGACGUUACAAUGGUGGAGUUGGCAGGUGUGCGCAGGCCAAGCAAUGGGGCUGGACACAAGGUCGGUGGCCCAAAAAGAGUGCUGAAUUUUUGCUGCACAUGCUUAAAAACGCAGAGAGUAAUGCUGAACUUAAGGGUUUAGAUGUAGAUUCUCUGGUCAUUGAGCAUAUCCAAGUGAACAAAGCACCUAAGAUGCGCCGCCGGACCUACAGAGCUCAUGGUCGGAUUAACCCAUACAUGAGCUCUCCCUGCCACAUUGAGAUGAUCCUUACGGAAAAGGAACAGAUUGUUCCUAAACCAGAAGAGGAGGUUGCCCAGAAGAAAAAGUUGAGGAGCUCAAGCUUGGGAAAAUGGUGUGCAUUCCUUGUAUCGUCAUUCCAGUUCUGCUCUGGAUCUACAAAAAAUUCCUGGAGCCAUAUAUAUACCCUCUGGUUUCCCCCUUCGUUAGUCGUAUAUGGCCUAAGAAAGCAAUACAAGAAUCCAAUGAUACAAACAAAGGCAAAGUAAACUUUAAGGGUGCAGACAUGAAUGGAUUACCAACAAAAGGACCAACAGAAAUCUGUGAUAAAAAGAAAGACUAAAGAAAUUUUCCUAAAGGACCCCAUCAUUUAAAAAAUGGACCUGAUAAUAUGAAGCAUCUUCCUUGUAAUUGUCUCUGACCUUUUUAUCUGAGACCGGAAUUCAGGAUAGGAGUCUAGAUAUUUACCUGAUACUAAUCAGGAAAUAUAUGAUAUCCGUAUUUAAAAUGUAGUUAGUUAUAUUUAAUGACCUCAUUCCUAAGUUCCUUUUUCGUUAAUGUAGCUUUCAUUUCUGUUAUUGCUGUUUGAAUAAUAUGAUUAAAUAGAAGGUUUGUGCCAGUAGACAUUAUGUUACUAAAUCAGCACUUUAAAAUCUUUGGUUCUCUAAUUCAUAUGAAUUUGCUGUUUGCUCUAAUUUCUUUGGGCUCUUCUAAUUUGAGUGGAGUACAAUUUUGUUGUGAAACAGUCCAGUGAAACUGUGCAGGGAAAUGAAGGUAGAAUUUUGGGAGGUAAUAAUGAUGUGAAACAUAAAGAUUUAAUAAUUACUGUCCAACACAGUGGAGCAGCUUGUCCACAAAUAUAGUAAUUACUAUUUAUUGCUCUAAGGAAGAUUAAAAAAAGAUAGGGAAAAGGGGGAAACUUCUUUGAAAAAUGAAACAUCUGUUACAUUAAUGUCUAAUUAUAAAAUUUUAAUCCUUACUGCAUUUCUUCUGUUCCUACAAAUGUAUUAAACAUUCAGUUUAACUGGUAGUUCAUUUUCUUUUAAAGUCUAUUGAAAUAUUCAAAAGGGAAAUUUUUCACCACGUCAGAAGGCAGAAUUUGGAUGUUGUGAUGGCAUCUGUGUAGUGGUGGGACAACAAUUACUAUUGUUGCGUAACAAGACACUCCAAAAUUUAGUGGUUUUCAGCAGCAGUGACUCGACUGGGCAGUUCUUUGCUGUUCUGGGCUCACUCAUAUGGCUGGCUGGGCCUGGGUCUGGACCUGGGCCGCUAUGUGAUUUUUAUCUUGGGCUUUGAAAAUUCAGUGUAGGGACCUAUAAAUAUUCAAAGAUGAUGAGAUGCAUCCUUAUAUAUUUUUUGUAUUCACUCUGAAGCUGGGAAAGAUUAAAAGGAACUCCUGCCCUUGGGUCCCUAAUGAAGUCUGGGUCCUAACUCAGGCUCUAUUAAGUUCUGUGGCUGGUCAAGUCACUGAUUUACCUUGGGCUUUAUUUGAUAUAAAUCAUGUAAAUCA